GUCUCACCUUCUCAUCCCCAGAUAAAAGCUGAGGAUGACCAGCCCCUCCCGGGAGUCCUCUUAUCCCUGAGUGGUGGCCUGUUUCGUUCCAACCUCUUGACCCAGGACAACGGCAUUCUGACAUUCUCAAACCUGAGCCCUGGCCAGUAUUACUUCAAACCCAUGAUGAAGGAGUUCCGGUUUGAGCCAUCCUCACAGAUGAUCGAGGUGCAGGAAGGCCAGAACCUGAAGAUCACCAUCACGGGGUACCGAACCGCUUACAGUUGCUAUGGCACAGUGUCUUCCUUAAACGGAGAGCCCGAACAAGGGGUUGCCAUGGAAGCGGUGGGCCAGAACGACUGCAGCAUUUACGGAGAAGACACCGUGACAGACGAAGAGGGCAAGUUCAGAUUACGUGGAUUGCUGCCGGGAUGUGUGUACCACGUUCAGCUCAAGGCAGAAGGCAACGACCACAUUGAGCGGGCGCUCCCCCACCAUAGGGUGAUUGAGGUUGGGAAUAAUGACAUCGAUGAUGUAAACAUCAUAGUUUUCCGGCAGAUUAAUCAAUUUGAUUUAAGUGGAAAUGUGAUCACUUCCUCUGAAUACCUUCCUACGUUAUGGGUCAAGCUUUACAAAAGCGAAAACCUCGACAAUCCAAUCCAGACAGUUUCCCUUGGCCAGUCCCUGUUCUUCCAUUUCCCCCCACUGCUCAGAGAUGGCGAGAACUAUGUUGUGCUUCUGGACUCCACACUCCCCAGAUCCCAGUAUGACUACAUCUUGCCUCAAGUUUCUUUCACCGCAGUGGGCUACCAUAAACACAUCACCUUGAUUUUUAAUCCCACGAGGAAGCUGCCUGAACAGGACAUCGCACAAGGAUCCUACAUUGCCCUGCCAUUGACGCUGCUGGUUCUGCUGGCCGGUUACAACCAUGACAAGCUCAUUCCUUUGCUGCUGCAGUUGACAAGCCGGCUACAGGGAGUCGGCGCGCUCGGCCAGGCAGCCUCUGACAAUAGCGGCCCAGAAGAUGCAAAGAGACAAGCCAAGAAACAGAAGACAAGGCGGACGUGAGGAGGAAGGGGACAGUUGCAGUCUCACUUGGGACAGGCCACAGCCAGGGGUCCGGCCACUACCCGCCCGUGGGAUAAAAGCCAAAAGCAUGCGUCAGCUAACUUCAGCCUGUGCUGCUGGGCCCGCACCCCAUGUCCCUUGUCACUGUGGCAUCCUGCACCCAUCCUCACCCCUCCGUAGAGCCCCUCGUGCAAUGCAAUGAAUGGACCCUCCUGUCACUCUGCUGAACAGAAUUUAUUUUCUGAGUCAAAUAUAAUUUAUUAUUAUUUUUGUCAAAGAAGUAUUUAAGCUGUGCUGUGGUGUGAGAAUGUCAUUCUUGAUCUUCAGCCUUCGUUUGCAAGAAGAGUUCCAGUUGAUGUGGUGUUUGGUUCCAUGGCGGGGUACCCUAGGGAUUCAUCUGUUUUCUUCACUUCCCUUUGCAUCUGAGAUCCUGCUGGAAACCACGGCAACCUGUAUCCACUAUUAGGAGGUAAAAAUCAAUAAAAUGGCCCAUUCAUUUGUGUUGUAGCUCA